ACCAGCCUCAGACACCACCAUGACCGGCUCCUGCUGCGGCUCCACCUUCUCCUCCCUGAGCUACGGGGGAGGCUGCUGCCAGCCCUGCUGCUGCCGCGACCCCUGCUGCUGCCGCCCCGUGACCUGCCAGACCACCGUGUGCCGCCCCGUGACCUGCGUGCCCCGCUGCACGCGCCCCAUCUGCGAGCCCUGCCGCCGCCCGGUGUGCUGCGACCCCUGCUCCCUGCAGGAAGGCUGCUGCCGCCCCAUCACCUGCUGCCCCUCGUCGUGCACGGCUGUGGUGUGCAGGCCCUGCUGCUGGGCCACCACCUGCUGCCAGCCUGUGUCUGUGCAGUCCCCCUGCGGCCAGCCGACCCCUUGCAGCACCACCUGCAGGACCUCCUCCUGCUGAGCCACCACCUGCUGCCAGCCUGUGUCUGUGCAGUCCCCCUGCGGCCAGCCGACCCCUUGCAGCACCACCUGCAGGACCUCCUCCUGCUGAGCAGCCCGUUAUCACGAAGGGCCCCUCAGAAGAUGGCCAGGUCCAUCCCGCUGCCCCUCAGGGCUUCACCGCAGAGCAAUACACGUUUCCUUGAGAAGCCCAUUUCUCAUCUCUUCAUACUAGCUCACACUAUGCAUUGAAGACACCUUUUCAGACCAACCACAGAUGAGAAAUACUUUUCCUAGGACUCCAGUCUAACUCCUAUAUCAUGUUGUCUGCUUUCUAAUAAACUCAAUACUCCUACCAUAGAAA